GUUCCCUCGUGAGGGACCUGAGGCCGACCGUAGCGGAUCUGAGAAGAUCCGAGAACACAGGCGAGUCGCGGAGGGGAGAACGCGAGAGGGCGUUGAGGUCUAGGUAUUCUAACGACAGAGGAGUUGGAGGUGCCAGAGAGGCAGCUGUGACCGCCUAGAGUUCUUGUUUGAAAUUCCUAGUGCCCGAAGGAGGAAACAGUGACAGACCUGGAGACUGCAGUUCUCUAUCCUUCACACAGCUCUUUCACCAUGCCUGGAUCACUUCCUUUGAAUGCAGAAGCUUGCUGGCCAAAAGAUGUGGGAAUUGUUGCCCUUGAGAUCUAUUUUCCUUCUCAAUAUGUUGAUCAAGCAGAGUUGGAAAAAUAUGAUGGUGUAGAUGCUGGAAAGUAUACCAUUGGCUUGGGCCAGGCCAAGAUGGGCUUCUGCACAGAUAGAGAAGAUAUUAACUCUCUUUGCAUGACUGUGGUUCAGAAUCUUAUGGAGAGAAAUAACCUUUCCUAUGAUUGCAUUGGGCGGCUGGAAGUUGGAACAGAGACAAUCAUCGACAAAUCAAAGUCUGUGAAGACUAAUUUGAUGCAGCUGUUUGAAGAGUCUGGGAAUACAGAUAUAGAAGGAAUCGACACAACUAAUGCAUGCUAUGGAGGCACAGCUGCUGUCUUCAAUGCUGUUAACUGGAUUGAGUCCAGCUCUUGGGAUGGACGGUAUGCCCUGGUAGUUGCAGGAGAUAUUGCUGUAUAUGCCACAGGAAAUGCUAGACCUACAGGUGGAGUUGGAGCAGUAGCUCUGCUAAUUGGGCCAAAUGCUCCUUUAAUUUUUGAACGAGGGCUUCGUGGGACACAUAUGCAACAUGCCUAUGAUUUUUACAAGCCUGAUAUGCUAUCUGAAUAUCCUAUAGUAGAUGGAAAACUCUCCAUACAGUGCUACCUCAGUGCAUUAGACCGCUGCUAUUCUGUCUACUGCAAAAAGAUCCAUGCCCAGUGGCAGAAAGAGGGAAAUGAUAAAGAUUUUACCUUGAAUGAUUUUGGCUUCAUGAUCUUUCACUCACCAUAUUGUAAACUGGUUCAGAAAUCUCUAGCUCGGAUGUUGCUGAAUGACUUCCUUAAUGACCAGAAUAGAGAUAAAAAUAGUAUCUAUAGUGGCCUGGAAGCCUUUGGGGAUGUUAAAUUAGAAGACACCUACUUUGAUAGAGAUGUGGAGAAGGCAUUUAUGAAGGCUAGCUCUGAACUCUUCAGUCAGAAAACAAAGGCAUCUUUACUUGUAUCAAAUCAAAAUGGAAAUAUGUACACAUCUUCAGUAUAUGGUUCCCUUGCAUCUGUUCUAGCACAGUACUCACCUCAGCAAUUAGCAGGGAAGAGAAUUGGAGUGUUUUCUUAUGGUUCUGGUUUGGCUGCCACUCUGUACUCUCUUAAAGUCACACAAGAUGCUACACCGGGGUCUGCUCUUGAUAAAAUAACAGCAAGUUUAUGUGAUCUUAAAUCAAGGCUUGAUUCAAGAACUGGUGUGGCACCAGAUGUCUUCGCUGAAAACAUGAAGCUCAGAGAGGACACCCAUCAUUUGGUCAACUAUAUUCCCCAGGGUUCAAUAGAUUCACUCUUUGAAGGAACGUGGUACUUAGUUAGGGUGGAUGAAAAGCACAGAAGAACUUACGCUCGGCGUCCCACUCCAAAUGAUGACACUUUGGAUGAAGGAGUAGGACUUGUGCAUUCAAACAUAGCAACUGAGCAUAUUCCAAGCCCUGCCAAGAAAGUACCAAGACUCCCUGCCACAGCAGCAGAACCUGAAGCAGCUGUCAUUAGUAAUGGGGAACAUUAAGAUACUCUGUGAGGUGCAAGACUUCAGGGUGGGGUGGGCAUGGGGUGGGGGUAUGGGAACAGUUGGAGGAAUGGGAUAUCUGGGGAUAAUUUUAAAGGAUUACAUGUUAUGUAAAUUUUUAUGUGACUGACAUGGAGCCUGGAUGACUAUCGUGUACUUGGGAAAGUCUCUUUGCUCUAUUUGCUGACAUGCUUCCUGUUGUGGUCUGGCCAAUGCCAAAUGUACUCGAAUGAUGUUAAGGGCUCUGUAAAACUUCAUACCUCUUUGGCCAUUUGUAUGCAUGAUGUUUGGUUUUUAAACAUGGUAUAAUGAAUUGUGUACUUCUGUCAGAAGAAAGCAGAGGUACUAAUCUCCAAUUAAAAAAUUUUUUAACAUGUAAGAAUUUUGUACUUUGAACAACAAGAUUACAGAAAGUACCUGUGGUUUUUGGAAAACAUUUCUAGCUUGGGGAAUGUGACAACAUUCCCCAGUGUGGUAAAAUUGGGGUAAAAUGUGGUAAAAUGUGAUACGCACAAACCCUUUGAAAAUAGCAAAACAAACAUGCCCUUUUUCUAAAAUUGAUAAAUCCUAAAGAGGAAGAAAAGAGCUGGGACAAUAAAACACUGGCUCUGGAAUCUGGAAUGUUAAGUCCAGGCCAGCAGUGACAAAAGUUAUUGUAAUGACCUCUGAACAGAGAAACACUGCCAUUGAAGAGGCUUCUGGUAUAGAAAACAUGGUACAUUCAGGAGCUGUGAAUAUAGCUCUAGGUGUGCUCCUGAAUCAGUUCAUGGUAGAUUAUGCUGAACAACAGUGAGAUGUUAUUGGAGGUGUGGAUGAGGGAGUUUGUUGUUGCAGUCCUUCUUUGCACCUUAUUUUAAAGAAUAAAUGAAACAUUUUUCUGGUUACUUUUUUAAAAAUUUAAAAUGGAAGGGAAGAAUAGGGGCAGGGCAUUAUUAGGCUAUUUCUGAUGCUUCAGUGUUAUAAAUUCAACAUAGAGGCUGACAACCUAAAUUCAUGGUGUAACACAGCUCUUUUCCUUUUCCUUUUUUUUUUUUUUUUGGUAUCUGUUCAAUGAAAAUAAGGUAUGACCCAAGUUUUUACCUAGUCUGACUAGAAGUAUUCCACUUCAAGGUCUGAAGUAGGACUUUUACCUUAAAAAACAACAACAAACAAAACUAUCACACAGGAUAGAUAAGAAGAUUGGUUAAACAGUUUUGUGUAGAUCUUUUUGGUGCUGAACUAUGACAUGAGCCUUAUAGAUUGUAAAAUAGGGAUAGUUGGAACUAAUGUACAGAACUAAAUUUUUUAAACUUUAUUUGCUGUUAAAUUCUGUGAAGUUUCAGUUAUCUAAAAUAAAUAUACACAAAUAUGAAAUAUAAUGUUUCAGAUUGCAAGGUAAUAUGUAAUAGUAGUGUUUGUAAGAUACUCUUGUCUAAUAUUAACUAGUAGUAUUUUGAUUUGUACAGUCAUAAUUUGUUAAAAUGACUUCAUUUAACAUUCACUGAUGUAGAUUAAUAAUGUAAGUUCUGAUUUAAAGAAUGGUGGCAAAAUGGUGCAUGUAAUACUUUUGCAAGUGUUGGGGAGAUCGGUAUGUUUUGAAAAGAGUAAUUUAACUUUUGGGUGCCAGGAAAUGGGUUUUCUCAAAGUCCAUUGCCGGCAAUGGGCAGGCCUGCAAAUACUGGCACAGAGCAUUAAUCAUACACCUUAUUAACGGUGAGGUGAAUAACUUUGAAAUAAAGUUUUAGAGAAAUGUUUCAGAUACUUGAGUAUUCUUUUUCACUCUUGAACUAACAACUUCGGCAAGAAAUCAGCUAAUAUUCUAUUUUUAAAUAUGGGCAUUAAUUUCAUUUCAGUUCGUUCACUCAUUCCAUUCAUUUAUCAUUUCACAAACAUUUGAAAUCCUAAUAUAAGCAAGGUGCUCUGUUUAAGGCAGAAAUUUGAAAAUGUACAAGAUAUAUGGUCUUGUCUUUAAGGAGCUGUUCAUCUAGAAUGGAGGAAUUUACACUGAUAAUUAUUCCUACACUUGAAACAAAGAAAUUAACUCUCAAAUUGCGUGGCAAGCAUAUAUAGACUUUGCUAUAAAUAUUUAUGAAAUGAGUUACUGUUUUCCUUAAAAAAGCUAAGACUAAGGGCUGGCAAUCAAAUAAGAGCAAAUUUAGUGGUGAACGUAGAACUGCCCACUACCAGCUAGAGUCUCCAACCUAAAAGUCCCAUGUUGCUAGUGAUCCCCAGGGGUUUUAUAGAAGGAAUCCCUGCAUUGGCAGUAAUUUUGGAUUAGAUGAUCCCUAAGAGCACCAUCAAGUCUUAGGAUUCUAUGAAUUAGGAAAUAAACCAAAUUAUAUAUUUUCUAAUACUGAUCAGCUCAUAUUUUAUCAUCAUGUCAUGUCUGGCUUUCAUACUUAGUCAUAAUUUACUUUCUGGGUCAUUUAGAGGCUAGCGUUCUCUAAGGUCACUUCUGCUUGCACAUUGUAGGAUAUUAUUUAGUAUGGCUUUAAGAAUUCAAUCUUUCCCCCUCUCCUUUAUGGAAUGUGUGUUUCCUCUAUUUGUACACUUAACCUUUUGUCCUAAGUUUUUAUUUUUAUGGAUACUAAUGAGUAACUUUGAGGUUGACACUAGACCCAAACAGAUGCAAACAGCCACUUUCUGUCCUCUUGUGACACAGUUGAAACACUUUAUCUCUUGUCUGCUGUUUGGAGUGUCCUGAAAGAAACACUGAAGUGGCAGUCAACAGAGCAAGGGUAACAGGAUCUUUAAAUAAUUUAAAGUUGUCUGAUCUUGACAUAAAAGUGAACCCUUUCUUUAAAAUUUCUAGCAACUGCUCUUAAGUCAUAGGUUCCUCAUUUUUUCUUUGCUGGUAGUGGGAGAAAAUAGUUGAUCUGUGAUUUUUGUUUUCAUCUCCCCAAACUAUGUUAUAAAGGCAGUAAUUUGAUGCUGAAGAUUAUGAUUAGAAAUCCUCAGAUGGGUUAUAUAUUGGGGCUUUAUCUUUUAAUAUUAAAAAGAAUGUCUUUCCUGGACUACUUUAUUCAGUAGUAAGCACUAUUCAUUCUAUGUAUAUUCCUUAUUCAGCCUUGCAGACUCCUGUGGGAUCUGAUCUCUUCCUGCUUCAACUCAGUACCAUACUCACCAAGGCUUAGUAUGUCUUCACCCACUCUCCCUUCUCUUGCAUUCCUCAAACAUGCUGAGUUUAUUCCAGCCUUAAGCCUUUGAUCUACGCAUCAGAAAUGUUGGGCCCCACUUCAGAUCUUCUCUGCCCUGCCUUCUACUCCAGUCACUGCUGUGGUAACUAAUUCCAUGAAGUCUUUGACCAGGUUCUCAGAGAAUAUGAUAGUACCUCUCUUUGGAUUCUAGCUGUAUACCUUUCACUUCAGCCUCCCUGACGUGGAAUGUCUGCAGAACUUGUUUGGUACUCCCAAUUGCACAGCCCAAAGGUGCAGGGGAGUUAGGUGCCCAUGGGGCCAUCCUUGACCUAGGUGGAAAGUUGCUAGUGGAUAACUGAUUACUCUUUUCAUCACCUGGGCAGACAGUUCUGAAAUGCAUUUCGUAAGUCUCCUCAAAAGAGGAGGAGACUUCUGUGGCGGGUUUGGCAAUAACCAUCCUUAUAUUGGCUUUCCUCUUUUGUUUCACUCCUGUGCAUCUCUCUUGCAUCCUGGGAUCGCUUCUCAAAUAAAUGACUUUCAUUCAA